AAGGAGCCCCCUGCCACCACCGACACCCACGGGCGGAGAUCACCUGCUGCCCCGCAGACCCCUGUCCCUUCCUCCCGGACCAGCAGCUAGAGCUCUCCGCCCUCACCGUGGUUUUAGCAGUCCUAGGGAAAGUGCCAGCCGAGACCAGCCAGACCAAGUCAGAGUACUGUGGAACCUGGAUUCCUGGGGAAUGGGGUCCCCAUGAGGAACUCCACAUUGGACUAAGAACAGACCCUGUUCCUGGAAGCAGCAGGAAACCAUCUCUGGUGUUAGAACUUCAGGCAUCUUGAAACACUCUGAAGCCGGGGGCAAUCUUUUCAGGAUGUCCAAACGGAGUUGGUGGGCUGGAUCCAGAAAGCCCCCAAGAGAGAUGCUGAAACUCUCAGGCUCUGACUCCAGCCAAAGCAUGAAUGGCCUUGAAGUGGCUCCCCCAGGUCUGAUCACCAACUUCUCCCUGGCCACGGCAGAGCAAUGUGGCCAGGAGACGCCACUGGAGAACAUGCUGUUCGCCUCCUUCUACCUUCUGGAUUUUAUCCUGGCUUUAGUUGGCAAUACCCUGGCUCUGUGGCUUUUCAUCCGAGACCACAAGUCCGGGACCCCGGCCAACGUGUUCCUGAUGCAUCUGGCCGUGGCCGACUUGUCGUGCGUGCUGGUCCUGCCCACCCGCCUGGUCUACCACUUCUCUGGGAACCACUGGCCAUUUGGGGAAAUCGCAUGCCGUCUCACCGGCUUCCUCUUCUACCUCAACAUGUACGCCAGCAUCUACUUCCUCACCUGCAUCAGCGCCGACCGUUUCCUGGCCAUUGUGCACCCGGUCAAGUCCCUCAAGCUCCGCAGGCCCCUCUACGCACACCUGGCCUGUGCCUUCCUGUGGGUGGUGGUGGCUGUGGCCAUGGCCCCGCUGCUGGUGAGCCCACAGACCGUGCAGACCAACCACACGGUGGUCUGCCUGCAGCUGUACCGGGAGAAGGCCUCCCACCAUGCCCUGGUGUCCCUGGCAGUGGCCUUCACCUUCCCGUUCAUCACCACGGUCACCUGCUACCUGCUGAUCAUCCGCAGCCUGCGGCAGGGCCUGCGUGUGGAGAAGCGCCUCAAGACCAAGGCAGUGCGCAUGAUCGCCAUAGUGCUGGCCAUCUUCCUGGUCUGCUUCGUGCCCUACCACGUCAACCGCUCCGUCUACGUGCUGCACUACCGCAGCCAUGGGGCCUCCUGCGCCACCCAGCGCAUCCUGGCCCUGGCAAACCGCAUCACCUCCUGCCUCACCAGCCUCAACGGGGCACUCGACCCCAUCAUGUAUUUCUUCGUGGCUGAGAAGUUCCGCCACGCCCUGUGCAACUUGCUCUGUGGCAAAAGGCUCAAGGGCCCGCCCCCCAGCUUCGAAGGGAAAACCAACGAGAGCUCGCUGAGUGCCAAGUCAGAGCUGUGAGCGGGGGGCGCCGUCCAGGCCGAGCGCAGACUGUUUAGGACUCAGCAGACCCAGCAAGAGGCAUCUGCCCUUUCCCCAGCCACCUCCCCAGCAAGCAACCUGAAAUCUCAGCAGAUGCCCACCAUUUCUCUAGAUCGCCUAGUCUCAACCCAUAAAAAGGAAGAACUGACAAAGGGGAUCCAUCGGCCACCCCUCUGCAGGGGCUUGUGAUGGCUACAAUGGCUCCUAGACACUCAACGACUUCAUCUGUGGCAGGGAGAGAGGAGGCCGGAAGAACAACCCCUGAACAAUGGAGGCCUUUCUUUCCCGCUAGGCUCCCAGCCUCCUUCCCGCUACAGAAUCGCUCAUCGGCGAGGCUCAGCAGAAAGACCCUGAAGGCAGGCUGCAAAUGACCCAGAAGAGGGACCUGGGAGUCCUGGUGGGGACGGGGAGGGAGUCUCAAUACUCCUUUGCAGUGCAAGGUACUCUGAGUCCCCUCUGUAGUGCCUCUGCCAGACACACACUGCCUGAGUUGAAGAGACACAGGCCACACAUUUCAGGCUGGUUGCCAGCGGACGUCAGCACUCACGGCCUGCAGGGACUCAGCACAGCUCUGGAUUCUGGAUCUCUCCUGCUGUAACCCCACGCACAAGCCUGCAACCCCCAGAGCUCUUUGACAGGCUCCCAGGCCUCCCAGUCCUGGACAAGCAUGUGCAGUCACGGGAGCUCAGCUCAGGCCAGGGCUGGGCUGUGCACCUGCCUCCCACUGACCCAGACCCACUUCCUCCAGAGAGGCCUCUCUCCGCCUGAGCUAUUUCCCUUGCUAGUGUGCAGAUAUUUCCCUAACAUGUCCUUUUUUGUAUUUGUUUGUACGGACCAUAAAUAUAACUGUAGCUUUAAGACUA